AUUGGUUGCAAAACCUUGAUCUGUGAAAGCGGGCGUUUUGGAAGAUACCGGAAGUAGAGUCACGGAGAGGUAGGAUCCGGAAGUGGGGCUGCCUCUUUAAAUAACAAAAAUCUGAGGUAUUAAGAAAUGGAGAGAAAAAUAAGCAGAAUCCACCUUGUUUCUGAACCCAGUAUAACUCAUUUUCUACAAGUAUCUUGGGAGAAAACACUGGAAUCUGGUUUUGUUAUUACACUUACUGAUGGUCAUUCAGCAUGGACUGGGACAGUUUCUGAAUCAGAGAUUUCCCAAGAAGCUGAUGACAUGGCAAUGGAAAAAGGGAAAUAUGUUGGUGAACUGAGAAAAGCAUUGUUGUCAGGAGCAGGACCAGCUGAUGUAUACACGUUUAAUUUUUCUAAAGAGUCUUGUUAUUUCUUCUUUGAGAAAAACCUGAAAGAUGUCUCAUUCAGACUUGGUUCCUUCAACCUAGAGAAAGUUGAAAACCCAGCUGAAGUCAUUAGAGAACUUAUUUGUUAUUGCUUGGACACCAUUGCAGAAAAUCAAGCCAAAAAUGAGCACCUGCAGAAAGAAAAUGAAAGGCUUCUGAGAGAUUGGAAUGAUGUUCAAGGACGAUUUGAAAAAUGUGUGAGUGCUAAGGAAGCUUUGGAGACUGAUCUUUAUAAGCGGUUUAUUCUGGUGUUGAAUGAGAAGAAAACAAAAAUCAGAAGUUUGCAUAAUAAAUUAUUAAAUGCAGCUCAAGAACGAGAAAAGGACAUCAAACAAGAAGGGGAAACUGCAAUCUGUUCUGAAAUGACUGCUGACCGAGAUCCAGUCUAUGAUGAGAGUACUGAUGAGGAAAGUGAAAACCAAACUGAUCUCUCUGGGUUGGCUUCAGCUGCUGUAAGUAAAGAUGAUUCCAUUAUUUCAAGUCUUGAUGUCACUGAUAUUGCACCAAGUAGAAAAAGGAGACAGCGAAUGCAAAGAAAUCUUGGGACAGAACCUAAAAUGGCUCCUCAGGAGAAUCAGCUUCAAGAAAAGGAAAAAAAAAUCAGAAAACCCACAGAAACAAAAGAAUGAGCAUAUGGGAAACUCGUAAUCCCACCCACCUGGAGAUGACCACCGUUGAGACCUGGUACUCUGUGUCGUUGCAGAUCCCUCUCUCUUCCACACUUCAUUGACAAAACUAGGCUCACACCAGUUAUGCUGUAACCCACAACUUUUUUUUUCUUCCAUUUAGCAAUCAAUAUGGUGUAAUAUGGGAGGAAAAUAAUAUCUUUGGAAGACUAUGUUUUAAAAGCAGUUGAUUAAUUUGAGAUAUGUAAUACUUUAUAUAUAGAGAGAGUUAUACAUGGAAUUACACAUAUAUUACACAUACAUGUAUGUAUGUUUUGCCAGAAUUUCUCCAGGAAGGCUAUAACAAUUUGUACCCUCACAACAGUGUUUGCCUUUUGAGUUUUUUGUUGUUGUUGUUUACCAAUUCAUUUUAGAAAUACAUAUAUAGAGAGAAGGAGAUGAAAUUGCAUGUGCCAACUUAAAAUGAGGUAGUUGACCAUUCCAUCUUUUCAAAAAGAAUUUAUUUUCAUACCUUGAUUCUUAAAAAUUGCUAGCAAUGUAUUCAAAGUUUAAAUCUCAAAGUAUUUGAAAAUUAUGUUUUUUAAAUUUAGAUGGAUAAUAUAAUCAUCAAAUUCAAAUAUCCAAUUUUUGUAGAUUUUUGGUACCUGAACUAUAGACUUUUUAAAUGUCAAAUUAGGUACAUAAAAUGAAUGUUCAAUUGCUAUAUAUUUACUCUGGUCAUCAUGAGCAAACCUCAUUUUUUACACAACUUUAAUUUUAUCAUAAUGUUUAUCUUAGUUGCAAAAGUAAACAUGGUGGUGGUUUUAAAACGAGAUAGGUUUUUAUUAGCUUCACUCUAUGUUUACCUAACUGGUCAGGCUGCGGCUCUCACUUUGCUUGCUGCAUAUUUUGAUUAAUGGCCCCUUGGCCUUGUUCCAGAGUAUACUGAUUAUGGUCAGUGCACUUCAAAGAUGAUUUAUUAAUUGUGUUUGUGACCCAAAAUAAUUCAAUAAAGAUUGAUCAUAUGCAUUAUUAUAGAUUUGCCAAUAAAAUCAACAGUUACACUUUAAGAGUAUGUUUGCCUGAAUAGAUUUUUUAAGUAUACAAAAAGGACAAAAACUUUUUUUUAAUGUAUUCUGUAUUAAACACAGAUUUAUGACCUUUUAAAGCAUGAUUAUUAAAUGUAUCAUAGGAUUGGUCUUGUAAGUGCAUGAAUUGUAAGUUCUACUUUAACAUAAUUUCAAGAUAAUAUGUUUCAUUGGAGCUUACAUAGGUGUUUUAAUAAAUAUUUCGAUGUUUAUAACACCCUGGGAACAACCCUUACUACAAUUCCCCUAGGCUAUUACGUACAUUUAAAUUUUAAAUUACUGACAGACUCAGAUGUCUGUUUUUAAAAAAAAUGUUUAUAGGAGACUUUUAUAAUCUUUCUGAGUUUUAAGUAAAGGGGAUUUAUCGUAUGUUUCCUAUAUGUUAUACUCUUGUCAUUUGAAAGACUUUGAUAUGUACAAUUUCUCUAAAUUUGGCUUGAUAAUAGUUAUUGUUUCAGGCAUUUUAAGCACUCUACCAACAUAGAAUAAUGUGUAAAUAUUCACUAUACAUGGCCGGCAAAGUUAUUAAUCAAAGGAAAUGACUCCCCGCUCAUAAUUUAUGGUUCAGUAUUAAAGGAAAAAUAGGAGGUAUAUAUUUUUUGGUAUACUGUAUCCAAAAUUUACACUGUAACAGUGAAAUUCUGUAACUUAAAUCAUCUAGUAUGAUGUGUUACUCAAUGUAAAGUAAGUAUUUGGUCCGUAGUAAAAAUUAUGAAAUAAAAUAAAAUAUUUUACCCACUAGAAA